ACUCCGCGGCCGCCGGGAGACACGCCGCCAUGCUGCAGAAGCGGGAGAAGGUGCUGCUGCUGAGGACCUUCCAGGGCCGCACGCUGCGGAUCGUGCGCGAGCACUACCUGCGGCCCUGCGUGCCCUGCCACAGCCCGCUCUGCCCGCAGCCCGCCGCCUGCAGCCACGAUGGGAAACUCUUGUCUAGUGAUGUGACUCAUUACGUGAUCCCAGACUGGAAAGUUGUUCAAGAUUAUCUUGAGAUCCUUGAGUUUCCUGAGUUGAAGGGAAUUAUUUUCAUGCAGACAGCUUGUCAAGCUGUGCAGCAUCAAAGAGGCAGGAGACAGUAUAACAAACUGCGAAACCUGCUGAAGGAUGCGCGUCAUGAUUGCAUUCUCUUUGCUAAUGAAUUCCAGCAAUGCUGCUAUCUGCCACGGGAAAGAGGAGAGUCCAUGGAGAAGUGGCAGACCAGGAGCAUAUACAACGCAGCUGUUUGGUACUAUCAUCACUGCCAGGACAGGAUGCCAAUUGUUAUGGUGACAGAAGAUGAAGAGGCAAUUCAGCAGUAUGGAAGUGAAACAGAAGGAGUAUUCGUGAUUACUUUCAAGAAUUACCUGGACAAUUUCUGGCCUGAUUUAAAAGCUGCCCACGAGCUUUGUGAUUCUAUCCUUCAGUCUCGACGGGAGAGAGAGAAUGAGAGUCAGGAGAGCCAUGGGAAGGAGUACCCAGAACAUCUUCCCCUGGAAGUGUUAGAAGCUGGGAUUAAAUCUGGACGCUAUAUCCAGGGAAUUCUGAAUGUCAACAAACACAGAGCCCAAAUAGAAGCUUUUGUUCGACUUCAAGGAGCCAGCAGUAAAGAUUCAGAUUUAGUCAGUGACAUCCUAAUCCACGGGAUGAAGGCUCGAAACCGCUCAAUUCAUGGAGAUGUGGUAGUUGUGGAGCUGCUUCCUAAAAAUGAAUGGAAAGGAAGAACCGUAGCCCUGUGUGAGAAUGACUGUGACGACAAGGCUUCGGGCGAGUCCCCAAGUGAGCCCAUGCCUACAGGUCGAGUGGUGGGCAUACUUCAGAAGAACUGGCGGGAUUAUGUGGUGACAUUUCCGUCCAAAGAAGAGGUCCAAUCUCAGGGCAAAAAUGCUCAGAAAAUCCUGGUUACACCUUGGGAUUACAGAAUUCCCAAAAUUCGAAUUAGCACUCAGCAAGCAGAAACCCUCCAGGACUUCAGGGUGGUCGUGCGCAUCGAUUCCUGGGAGUCAACAUCUGUGUAUCCAAAUGGACAUUUUGUGCGUGUUUUAGGAAGAAUCGGAGAUCUGGAAGGGGAAAUUGCAACCAUCCUGGUGGAAAACAGUAUUUCAGUUAUUCCUUUCUCAGAAGCUCAGAUGUGUGAGAUGCCAGUAAACACACCAGAAAGUCCCUGGAAGGUGAGUCCUGAAGAGGAACAAAAACGUAAAGACUUGAGGAAAAGCCAUCUCGUAUUCAGCAUUGACCCCAAAGGUUGUGAAGAUGUGGAUGACACACUCUCAGUCAGAACCUUAAAUAAUGGCAACCUGGAACUUGGGGUCCACAUCGCAGAUGUAACACACUUUGUGGCACCAAAUUCUUACAUUGAUAUUGAAGCUAGAACAAGGGCCACCACUUAUUAUCUAGCAGAUCGUCGCUAUGACAUGCUGCCUUCCGUCCUCAGUGCAGAUUUGUGUUCCCUUCUGGGAGGCGUUGAUAGGUAUGCUGUAAGCAUCAUGUGGGAACUGGAUAAAGCCUCUUAUGAAAUUAAGAAAGUGUGGUAUGGCAGAACCAUUAUUCGAUCAGCAUACAAACUGUUCUAUGAAGCAGCCCAAGAACUACUGGAUGGAAACUUAAGCGUUGUUGAUGAUAUUCCAGAAUUCAAAGACUUGGAUGAGAAGAGCAGACAAGCCAAGCUGGAGGAGUUGGUGUGGGCAAUUGGAAAGCUGACCGACAUAGCUCGCCAUGUCAGAGCUAAACGAGACGGAUGUGGUGCCCUGGAACUGGAAGGGGUAGAGGUUUGCGUACAGCUAGAUGACAAAAAGAACAUUCACGACCUCAUCCCCAAGCAGCCCCUGGAAGUCCACGAGACAGUGGCUGAAUGCAUGAUCCUGGCCAACCACUGGGUCGCCAAAAAGAUCUGGGAGAGCUUCCCUCAUCAGGCCUUGCUGCGCCAGCACCCUCCUCCACACCAGGAGUUCUUUUCAGAACUCCGGGAAUGUGCUAAAGCCAAAGGCUUCUUCAUAGAUACACGGUCCAAUAAAACACUGGCUGAUUCUCUGGAUAAUGCGAACGACCCCCACGAUCCCAUUGUGAACAGGCUACUGCGCUCCAUGGCCACGCAGGCCAUGUCGAAUGCUCUGUACUUCUCCACCGGAUCCUGUGCGGAGGAGGAGUUCCAUCAUUACGGUCUUGCAUUAGAUAAAUAUACCCACUUUACUUCUCCAAUAAGAAGAUAUUCAGAUAUUGUAGUACACCGCUUGUUAAUGGCAGCCAUUUCAAAAGAUAAGAAAAUGGAAAUUAAGGGAAAUCUGUUCAGCAACAAAGAUCUUGAGGAAUUAUGCAGACAUAUCAACAACAGAAACCAAGUGGAAAUGUAAAGAUUCAAGCAACGCAUAAAGAUAUGAUGACAGAGGCCAGACGUGGUGGCUCACUUGAGGGCGGAUCACUUGAGGUCAGGAAUUUGAGACCAGCCUGGCCAAUAUGGUGAAACCCCAUCUCUACAAAAAAUACAAAAAUUAGCCGGGUGUGAUGGCACGCGCCUGUAGUCCCAGUUACUUGGGAGGCUGAGGCAGGAGAAUCUCUUGAACCCAGGAGGUGGAGAUUGCAGUGGGCCGAGAUCACACCACUGCACUCUAGCCUGGGUGACAAAAUUGAGACUGUGUCUCAAAAAAAAAAAAAGAUAUGAAGACAGAAACAUCACCUGUUAUCUUACCACCCAGAGCUAACAAUUAAUGAUUCUAGACACUGCUAACAUUUUUAUUUAUAAAAAUAUCGGCCAGAUGCGGUGGCUUGCACCUGUAUUCCCAGUACUUUGGGAGGCUGAGGCAGGUGGAUCACGAGGUCAGGAGAUCGAGACCAUCCGGGCUAACACAGUGAAACCCCAUCUCUACUAAAAAUACAAAAAAUUAGCAUGGUGGCAGGCGCCUGUAGUCCCAGCUACUCAGGAGGCUGAGGCAGGAGAAUGGUGUGAACCCGGGAGGCGGAGCUUGCAGUGAGCUGAGAUUGCACCACUGCACUCUGGCCUGGGUGACAGAGCGAAACUCCGUCUAAAAAAAAAAAAUCACACCGUGCCUGCUGUUUGAAUCUGCUUUUUUCAUGUAACCCAACUGUUAUUGAUAGCACACCAUGUUAUAUCAUUGUUUUGAAGCUGCUUUCUAUUCUAUUUCAUAUUACUAGUUGCUACAAGAUUGCACAGCAUAGAACUAGACUAUUGGGUAACGCAGGAAAUUGGAAACUACCUAAAUGUUUAAUGUAAUUUUCUAUAUCCAAUGGUAUAGUUGUCUGCUGUGCAAUGUUGUAGCACUAGCCAUGUGGACUACCUAAAUUUAAUUAAAAUUAGAAGUAGAAAUUUGUCUCAGUAGAAAUUUGGCCAGUGUCUCAGUCACACUGGCCACAUUGUAUAGCUCAGUGGCCACUUGUGGUUAGUGGCUACAUAUUAGGCAACACAGAUAGAGAGCAUUUCUAUCAUUGCAGAAAGUUCUGUUGGGCAGCACUGUUCUAAGCAAUCAAAUUUAUAACCAUCCUUAUGGAUACACUUAUACAGACAUUUCAGAUGAUUUCCUGGAAAAAUUCCUAGAAAUGGAAUUGCUGAGCCAAAAGGUGUGCAUGCACAAAUGAAACUGAUAGGUCAGGUGCAGUGGCUCACGACUGUAAUCCUAGCACUUUUCGAGGUCGAGGCCGGUGGAUCACCUGAGUUCAGGAGUUCCAGAGCAGCCUGGCCAACAUGGUGAAACCCCGUUACUACUAAAAAUACAAAAAUUAGCCAGGCAUGGUGGUGCAUGCCUGUAAUCCCAGCUAAUCGGGCGGCUGAGGCAGGAGAAUCACUUGAACCCGGGAGGCAGAGGUUGCAGGGAGCCAAGAUCGCGCCAUUGCACUCCAGCCUAGGCGAUAGAGUGAGACUCCAUCUCAAAAAGAAGACAAAGAAACUUUAAUACAUAUUACUAAAUUGUCUUCCUUAUCAGUAGUGCUAAUUUAGACUUCCACCAAUAGGGUUUUCAUUGGACAGGCUUGAAAAGAAAGAAAGGCUGGCCGGGCGCGGUGGCUCAUGCCUGUAAUCCCAGCACUUUGGGAGGCCGAGGCAGGCGGAUCACGAGGUCAGGAGAUCAAGACCAUCCUGGCUAACACAGUGAAACCCCAUUUCUACUAAAAAUACAAAAAAUUACCCGGGCGUGAUGGCAGGCGCCUGUAGUCCCAGCUACUCCAGAGGCUGAGGCAGGAGAAUGACGUGAACCCAGGAGGUAGAGCUUGCAGUGAGCCGAGAUUGCACCACUGUACUCCAGCCUGGGUGACAGAGUGAGACUCCAUAUCUCAAAAAAAAAAAGAAAUGCAAGUAAGACAUGUGUAAUACUUUUCCUGUACCCAAGGUGAACAUGACCCAAAUUUGCUGAUCUCUAAUUUCAUGAACUAUAAAUGGGUUUCAUUUUAUAAAAUAAUUCAUUUUCUAAGACAUUUUUGAGGAGAUAAUACUAGAUGGUUAAGUUCCCACAAAAAGUAAUUUAAUUUCAUAGUAGAGAACAAUUUUUAUAUUAAUAGUUUUACAGAAUCUCACAUUUGAAUGAAUAUGAAUUUCGUUUCUUUGGGGAAUGCCAGGGGAGUGUUAAAAUGCUUUGGAGUUGUGCUUC